GCUUCCGGCACAGCGGAACUCCGGGUGCCGGUUGAGGUUGCUGGUGGACCUGCUCUGGUGGUCUUGGAUGAGGCCCCAUGAGCGCGGCGCCCCUGGUGGGCUACAGCAGCAGCGGCUCCGAGGAUGAGUCCGAGGACGGGAUGCGGACCAGGCCGGGGGAUGGGAGCCACCGUCGUGGCCAGAGCCCCCUUCCCAGGCAGAGAUUUCCAGUACCUGACAGUGUGCUGAACAUGUUCCCGGGCACCGAGGAGGGGCCUGAAGAUGACAGCACAAAACACGGGGGACGGGUGCGCACCUUCCCCCACGAGCGAGGCAACUGGGCCACCCACGUCUAUGUACCAUAUGAAGCCAAGGAGGAGUUCCUGGAUCUGCUUGAUGUGUUGCUGCCCCAUGCCCAGACAUAUGUCCCCCGGCUGGUAAGGAUGAAGGUGUUCCACCUCAGCCUGUCCCAGAGUGUGGUUCUGCGCCACCACUGGAUCCUCCCCUUCGUGCAGGCUCUGAAAGCCCGUAUGACCUCCUUCCACAGCCCCCAUCCAGGACCUCAUUGCCUCAUUGGAACCAAAGAUGCCCCUGUCACCCAGGAAAUUCCAAAGGAUUUAGGAGCUCUGCGUCAGGAGCCAGGAUCACAGACCAGAUAAUAGAACAAAAGAUGCUCCUAGCACCCCUGCUGCUUAGGAAAUGACACAGGUUUUAGGAUCUCUGUGUCAGGAACUGGAGGCUGAGACCAACACAUAUGUUAUCAUUUCACAGUGAUAGGUCAAACAGGUCAUGGUAAUGGUGGGAGCUACCUCACUGGGGGCCUAUGGGGGUGAAAGGAGAUCAUGGGUGCCCUCAGCACACCACUUGGGUGAAGGGUUAGUACCAGACCCCACUUCUGGUUUUGUCUGCCAGCCUGGGGCUUUUUUUUUCCCCUUACCUAUUAGAUUAUUUCAUAACUCUUUUCCUACCAGAAAUGCAUCUCCUGCUAGACUGGUCCAGAUCAAAACCCUGCUCUUUCACUGAGGCUCUCCCGGUUGGCAUAUCCUGCAGAAUCCCUCCGUCCAGAGAUCAGUCGGUCCUGUGGUUGUUUCACAGGUGACUCCUCUGUCCAGAGAUCAGUCGGUCCUGUGGUUGUUUCACAGGUGACACCUCCGUCCAGAGAUCAGUUGGCCCUGUGGUUGUUUCACAGGUGACCCCUCCAUCCAGAGAUCAGUUGGUCCUGUGGUUCUUUACCCCUGGUGGUCAUUUCACUCACCCUCAUAUGCAGUCGUUCCUGUGUCCAUCUUCCUUCCUGGAGCCCACAUUCCUCCAGGCCAGGACUGUGGCUUCUCUCUGAAUUGCCCCACAGCUUUUUUCCAAGUGCUCUGCUCACAGUAGACAUCAAAUAGAUGCUUGUUGAGUCAUGGUGCGGGAAUGAGGGAGCCUAGAGAAUAUCUUUCUGGAUCCUCUACUGUUGAUACUAGAAGGAGCCUAAGAAGCCACCCGGCUGAUGGUUUUCUGACCCUGCCUUUAUCAGCAGAGCCUUUUUUCAAAUGAGGUGUUGCACAAAAGCCUGAUGUGUGGCUGUGUAAAACAGAAAUAAACAGUCUUCUAGCCAAAGCCCCAUUCCCACAGUUCAGGGGGCCAUAGGCCCAGGAAUUCCAUAGGAUGUCACUGCCCAACUAGGAAACUGCUCAGUUAGCUGAACCCCUUCUGAGGGCCAGAGGAGGACAGGAUUUGUCCCAAUCCAGACACUCGGCCAGGGAAUAAGGGCUGAAACUCAUCUCUCAACCUAGUCCAGCCCUCCCCCUCUUUGGAUUGUCAUUAUCAAGUUGAUUGAUUGUAUAUUAUCAGGACUCUCUUAACCACAGGUGCCAGAAGCCCAUGCCAGAAGCCCAACCCAAAGUGGCUUAAACCAAAGAGAAAUUUAUAGGCUGGUAUAACUAAAAGAUUCAGAGGUAGCACUGGCUCAUGCAUGAGUGGACCGGGGUGACAAGAUAUCAGAUGGCACCUGACUGUCACCACCACAGGCAGACUGUUCACCAUCUCAGCUCUGUCCCCUUCCUUUGUCACAAUGACGAAGCCACCGCAUCUCCCGGCUAAUGGUGUACCAGCCUGGAAAGACAGCCUCCCUCUCUGAUUGGCUUCAGCACAAGUCACAGGAAUGACUGCCUGGUCUGACCCGUCUCCUGUGUGCUUUCUUUGGGAGUAAAGAGUUAACAGGCCCUUCCCCCUUCCACAGAGAGUGCUUCCCUUAUCCUGCGGAAGCUCUGCCCCUGGAUGAAGGAGGAGAGCGGCUAUGUUAGUGCUGAUGACUGGCACACUGCACUUGCGCUAGGAAGACAGCAUGAACUGCACCCCUCCAGGGAAGCCACGGCCUGGGCUCCCCUGCAUACAGUGGUUCCUUAACUGGGCACGAGUCCCUUGCUGGGACUUAGGAAAACUCUGCCUAAAGUCCAUUGCAAGAAAUACUGAUCCCUGUGGGAUGUAUAUGUGGCUGGUUCCCUUGCUCACUGAGAGACUAGAAAACAGCACCUGGACCCCUGGGCUGGUUCCCUCUGAGGAAAGGAUCUGUGUCAUGAGUGAAGCCCGGGCAGGUGUGGUCUGUUCAACUUUGAUCAUCUGGUUGAGCCUAAGGUGACCAAGAGUGGGCGGUGCACCCCUGAUUCUGUUGCUGUGACUGAGGAAAUGCUAAGCUCUGUUUGGCCAGGCCUGGGCAGCCUGCCUCUGGAGUAGGGGUGGAGAGCCAUCCUGCAACACGAGGUUACCAGGAGAAGGAGUUUUGGUUGGGCACAGACAUCCAGUGUCCACUCCAGGAUGUUUGGGAGACACCUUGAGAACUCUUCCUAAAAGCUGCACUUAACCAAGCUCCUGGUGGUUCUGUGAUCCCUUACAUUUUCUCCAGAGGCAGAGAGUUGGCUGACUGACUUUUGCCCUUGGGCAGAUUGUGAGGCUCUACCCAGCAUGCUGGUAUAUUAUGUUCCCUCAGAUGGGGGUGAGACCCUUGGCCUGGGGGCUGUAAAAUGAUCUGUUUCUGUGAGGAGACUUUCCAUGGUGAGAUUGCUAGUGUCUCAGAGAAUAAAGGACAGAACCAGUCCAAGUCAAAGCA